GAGUUGGCGCCAGCUUCCUCGGAUGUAGAUAUUGCUGGCUGGAUGACCAGCCACAGCCAGCUAGCUUGAGUCCAAGGCCUCCUCAGGCACUGUGUUUCUGCUCUGUGGGCUGCAGCCCCAGUGGGGUGGCAUGUCACAGAGGAAGGCCAGAGGGCCACCAGCCAUGCCAGGGGUGGGGCAUAGCCAGACUCAGGCCAAAGCACGGUUGCUGCCAGGCGCUGACAGGAAGAGGAGCCGCCUCAGCAGGACAAGGCAGGACCCGUGGGAAGAAAGAAGCUGGAGCAACCAGAGAUGGAGCAGAGCUACCCCUGGCCCUCGAGGGACCAGGGCUGGGGGCCUGGCUCUUGGCAGGAGCGAGGCCAGUCCUGAGAAUGCCGCGCGGGAGCGGAGCCGGGUCAGGACGCUGCGCCAGGCCUUCUUGGCCUUGCAGGCUGCUCUGCCUGCCGUGCCGCCCGACACCAAGCUCUCCAAGUUGGACGUGCUGGUGCUCGCCGCCAGCUACAUAGCCCACCUCACCCGCACACUCGGCCACGAGUUGCCUGGCCCUGCCUGGCCGCCCUUCCUGCGUGGACUCCGCUACUUGCACCCUCUCAAGAAGUGGCCGAUGCGAUCUCGUCUCUAUGCUGGAGGCCUGGGGUACUCCGAUCUUGACUCCACCACAGCCAGCACCCCCAGCCAAAGAACAAGAGAUGCAGAGGUGGGGUCCCAAGUCCCUGGAGAGGCAGAUGCUCUCCUUUCCACCACACCACUCUCACCAGCUCUUGGUGACAAAUAAUUAUCACACUCGCCCUUUUCUCCUAGACUGUGACUCAUGCUUAUGGGCCUGGAUUUUCUACCAGCCCCCAGAUUCUCAGCCAUCAGACUUGACUCAGACUCAGCUCCCAAGUUCCAGCAUGCAGACCAAGAGAAGCAGUAGCACUUCUGUGAUGGACAGUACCUAGAGGGGCACAGGUUGGAGAGCCUCCUCCUUGGUCCCCAGGAGGGGACUUCCCCAUGGCUCUUCUGUGACAGCUACUGGGAAGUGGGAGAGAAAGAGGUAUAAUUGGGCUCAAAGUUGAGGUAGGGAACCACCCUAGCUUUCUUCCCCUAAGGUUUCUACAAACCCUCUGCAGAUAGCAAAAAGGCAGGUGCAGAGGGAGGGGCCUGGGAUGGCACCAGCCCCAGGUGCUGAUGGGAAAGCCAGGUGGCCGGAUAGGCUCCUGGUAGCUCCAAGUGUAAACAGAUCUGGGCUGGGUCACACAGCCAGAGGGGAAACUGAAGAAGGAAAUGUGCUUUCUAACUGCAUCAUGAGAUGCUUACCUGAUGUUAGAGAGAUAGUGAGGAAUUCAGGAUUCCUCCCUCUGUAGUAUGGGCCUUUCCAGAAGCUGCCCCUCACCACUACAUUUUCUCUCCCUCUCGGCUCCUGCACUCUUCCACUCUUUUCUUUUCUUUUCUUUUCUUUUCGUUUCUUCUUCUUUUUAUGUAGAGAUGGGGGUCUUGAUAUGUUGCCCAGGCUGGCCUCGAACCCCUGGCCUCAAGUGAUCCUCCCACCUCAGCCUCCUAAAGUGCUGGGAUUACAGGCAUGAGCCACCAUGCCCAACCCCACUGUUUUCUUGACAUGAGUUAUAUCUACAGGUUAAGCCAUACAUCUUGCAUUGCUUACAUUCCAGUUUCCAGAGAAACUUUUAGAUAGUCCCAGAUGCCUAGUUUGAGAUCUUAACCAGAAGCAAUUCUACCUUAAUUGAACCAAGCAGCAACUUAUGGCCUUAAAUAUGAAGGAUAUUGACAGAAUCAAUUACAUCCUUGAAGGACCUUAAGAGAAGAUCAGGUAUAUAGGGGGUGAUCAUUACAGUCUUCUCUUUCCAUUAUGUUAGAAACCUGCCCUCAAGCAAAAACAAGAUAGGCCUGCCUUCAACUGCUCAACCACUCAAUUGGCUCCUUGUAAAAUUUGUGUUCGAGGCUUCCCUGGCUCUGGAGUUAUUUCUAUAGUCUAUUAGCUCCCUAGGGCCGGCUCCGCCUCAUGGAGAUCGUCCUUGGGGGCUUUCUCUAAGUCCUACCAUGGGGUGCCAGAAAUGUGAUAUAGCUUCGGUGAAACUCAUCUCUGGCCCUAAAGAAAUAACUUGAGGACUAAUCAUAGAAUCUACACACACUGAAAAUAACUUUCCAGAUCGGAUGUAGCCUCAAACCUGGCACCUGAAGUCCAGAUGGAACAAAUUACCUUUCGGUUAAAUUUCAGCCCUUCAGAGUGGGAGGGGACGGGCAUGACCAACUAGAGUCCCAACAAGGUUAUCCUUAGACACACACCAUUGUUGUUAUCAUGAAUGUAAGUGAGCUCUGGGCAGGCUGGGAAUGGUUGGGGUCUGGGUUCUGGCAUGACAGGACCCUGUACCUCCACAGGGCUGGCCAGGGCAGAGCUGAAAUAGGGCUGGGGGUGCGACUGAGCCAGUUGUGGUAGAGGUAGAAAAAGAGACACAGAACAUCCCAGCCCCGAGCUGCCUGGGAUGUGGGAGAACAGCUGGAAUGUGGAUGGGAGCCAUGGGGAGAAGGCCUCGGCCAAGGCUGAACUCGUAAAUCUGCCUUGAACCACGUCUCUGCAGAGGGACCCUGAAGAGCUUGUGCAGAGCUGAUGUGGGCAGCUGGACAGGGCCAGGCAGGGGCAGAGGCCAGGUGUGGGAGGGCAUGAGCACAGUGUUCUUCACAAGACCAUAAAAGUCCAGCUAGAAUGUACUAUUUUUAAAGCCAAACAGCAGUAUCUUCCUGGUUGAGUUCACGGGAGUGCUAGGAAGAGAAGCAGAUACAUUUCCUCCUCAGUUGGUGGCACACUUUCCUGGGGAUGAAGGGAAAUUGGCUUGGGGUGUGUGUCGGGGUCCUCUGGAUAGCAUGGAGCUUCUCCUGAUAAUAGAGUAGACUUUGGGUUGGAGCUUGCCCCACCCUGUCCUGCUCAGACUCAGGCCUUUGCCUAGUAACAUUAGAGCCCUCAGGGGUGACCGCAUGGCCCUGGUGUAGACAAGGAGGGCACAGGAAGGAUGACGCAGGUGGAGGGCUGCAGGAGGCAGGUCCCAUCGCUACAAGUUUCUCAGGGUGUCUUGGGCCCUUUCCAGGCAAAGCUGUUCUCCUUUGUGCCCAGGACAGUCGAGGGGGGUGGGGCAGAGGCCAUCUCCUCCAGCCACAGAGACCCAGCCCCGUCAGGCCAGCAAGCAAAGGGGCCUGGCAGGGGGCAGGGUGAGCCAAGGGAAGGCCUAGGGGAUGGAUGGGAAUAACCAGAGGAUGGACUGGGCCCUCCCUCCCUGACAAGCACAGUAAUGCCCUUGAGACAUGUCAGGACUUGGAUGCGUGAAUGAACCAGAAGUAACCCGCUUUGUCUCUGCAAUGAGAAAGAAAAACACAGCCAGGCUCAGUGGCUCAUGCCUGUAAUCCCAGCACUUUGGGGAGUCGAGGCGGGCGGAUCAUGAGGUCAGGAGUUCGAGACCAGCCUCGCCAACAUGAUGAAACCCCUUCUUUACUAAAAAUACAAAAAUUAGCCAGAUGUCGUAGUGGGCACCUGUAAUCCUAGCUACUUGGGAGGCUGAGGCAGGAGAAUUGCUUGAACCUAGGAGGCGGAGGUUGCAGUGAGCCAAGAUCACGCCACUGCACUCCAGCCUGGGCGACAGAGCAAGACCCCAUCUCGGGAAAAAAAAAUGAAAGAAAAAAAAAGAAAAGAAAAGAAAUAAAAGAAAAUAUGGAUGAAAACAUUUGAGCAUGGAUGACAAAUGACACUAGGGUGGCCUGGCUCAGGAGUUGGAGGCUCAGCUGCUCCAUAGGGGAUUGGCCUGGCCUACCUGGUCUUCCUGCACCACCUGCCCCAUCCCCAGGACUUGGGAUUGGGAUGGAGGUGGAGGUGGGGAACAAGACUUCCCUGCUGGCUCCCUCCACAGAGCAUGUGCUUUCUGAGGAACAGGAUGGCAGGGUGGAGGCUUAGAUGGGGCUGUGGGGCUGGGUGUGGUGGCUGAUGCCUGUAAUCCCAGCACUUUGGGAGGCCGGGGUCGGGGGUGGAUCAUCUGAGGUCAGGAGUUCAAGACCAGCCUGACCAACAUGGUGAAACCCUGUCUCUACUAAAAAUACGAAAUUAGCUGGGUGUGGUGGCACAUGCCUAUAACCCCAGCUACUUGGGAGGCUGAGGCAGGAGAAUUGCUUGAUCCCAGGAGGUGGAGUUUGCAGUGAGCUGAGAUUGUGCCAUUGCACUCCAGCCUGGGCAACAAGAGUAAAACUCCGUCUAAAAAAAAAAAAAAAAUGCGGCUGUGGGAGAAGCAGAGCUGGCCCAGUGAUUUCUUUUUUUUUGUUUUUUGAGACAGAGUCUCACUCUGUCACCGAGGCUGGAGCGCAGUGGCGUGAUCUCGGCUCACUGCAAGCUCCGCCUCCUGGGUUCACGCGAUUCUCCUGCCUCAGCCUCCCGAGCAGCUGGGACUACAGGCACCCGCCAACACGCCCGGCUAAUUUUUUUUUUUUUUUGUAUUUUUAGUAGAGACGGGGUUUCACCAUGUUAGCCAGGAUGGUCUUGAUCUCCUGACCUCGUGAUCCGCCCGCCUCGGCCUCCCAAAGUGCUGGGAUUACAGGCAUGAGCCACCGCACCCGGCUGGCCCAGUGAUUUCUAAGUAAUACAGUGGACACUGGAUUUUACCAAAUUGGGAACUAGAGAAGUAGAGGAUCUAGCCUUCUCUGAGACUCCUUUUCUCUUCCUCUGGGAGGAGCCUGGCUAGGGUGAGUCAGAUGGCACUGUCCUCUCCCUUUUGUGGCAUGAGCCCUAAACCCAGGGCCCCUAAAAGCUUAUUCUAUUCUAGAUCAAGGUAGGCAAACUAUGGCCAGUGGGCCAAACCCAGCCCCCCAUGUAUUUUUGUAAAUAAAGUUUUAUUGGAACACAUCCACA